GGACUUGGGCGGCGCCUGGAUAAACACCUGAACCUGACUGAGCUCCGAGCCAGGGACUCGGGUGCCUGGGGCAGACGAGGCCGGCUUCUCCGCGGACAGCUAGGGAGAGUGUCCUGGGUGUCAGCCAGAACAUGUCUUUCAACCUGCAAUCAUCAAAGAAACUGUUCAUUUUCUUAGGAAAAUCACUGUUUAGUCUUCUGGAGGCUAUGAUUUUUGCCUUACUCCCAAAGCCACGGAAGAACGUUGCUGGUGAAAUAGUCCUCAUCACAGGUGCUGGAAGUGGACUCGGAAGGCUCUUAGCCUUGCAGUUUGCCCGGCUGGGAUCUGUUCUUGUUCUCUGGGAUAUCAAUAAGGAGGGGAAUGAGGAAACAUGUAAGAUGGCUCGGGAAGCUGGAGCCACAAGAGUGCACGCCUAUACCUGCGAUUGCAGCCAAAAGGAAGGAGUGUAUAGAGUAGCCGACCAGGUUAAAAAAGAAGUCGGCGAUGUUUCCAUCCUAAUCAACAAUGCCGGAAUCGUAACAGGCAAAAAGUUCCUUGACUGUCCAGAUGAGCUUAUGGAAAAGUCAUUUGAUGUGAAUUUCAAAGCACAUUUAUGGACUUAUAAAGCCUUUCUACCUGCUAUGAUUGCUAAUGACCAUGGACAUUUGGUUUGCAUUUCAAGUUCAGCUGGAUUAAGUGGAGUAAAUGGGCUGGCAGAUUACUGUGCAAGUAAAUUUGCAGCCUUUGGGUUUGCUGAAUCUGUAUUUGUAGAAACAUUUGUCCAAAAACAAAAGGGGAUCAAAACCACGAUUGUGUGCCCCUUUUUUAUAAAAACUGGAAUGUUUGAAGGUUGUACUACAGGCUGUCCUUCUCUGUUGCCAAUUCUGGAACCAAAAUAUGCAGUUGAAAAAAUAGUAGAAGCUAUUCUACAAGAAAAAAUGUACUUGUAUAUGCCAAAGUUGUUAUACUUCAUGAUGUUUCUUAAAAGGCUUCAUCUGGCACAGGAUGGGUCAGAAUGCCUGACUGAGGCUAUGUGGGACAGAGCAAAGGAUCCUGGACAAGCAAUUCGAAAUUCAGGCUUACGAUCCCACUAUUCACUAAGUCUGUGACUCUGAGCGUGCCCUUUAUUCUCCAGCUUUUUGCCCCUCAAGACAGGACUGCUUAUAGCUGACUAUUUGGGCAUCCUUCAUGCAAUGGAUGGCUUUGUUGACCAAAAGAAGAAGCUCUAAAGACCAACUCUAUGGCUAAGGUCAUCUGAUACACAGUGUUACAUAAUGCGUACUUCAAUGAAGAAAAGUAUUUUUGUCUGACAGUGGAAUAUAUCUGGAGACCACAAGUACCACUCCUAUUCUGUUAUCUGGACUAGAAUUUUCAAUCAAUGUGUUUGAAAAUAAUGUUGCUAUCACCUAUUUGGUUGAGUUUUGGUUUUUUCUUUUUCUUUUUUUUUCCAAAAAUAAAGACAGCCCAUUUUUGUCAUUUCCAUUACCACAGAUGUAAGAAAGUGAUAAGCCAUGGCCAUGAGCUGCCCUGAGCUUUGGUCGUUGGGGAGGUGGCUCAAAUGGAGCCAGCGGCUGUGGUUGACCUGCCUUGGGGAGCAGGGCUGAGGGGCGAAGAGGACAUGUGGAUAUCCAGCCAGAAUGCCCUCUCUCCAGAGGACACACAGCUCUGGAUUUCUACCCCCUUGCUAUCCUCUCUGGCCAUUUUGAACCUGUACCACCUAAUGUAGAAAAGGCCCGCCUCCAGUGCCCUUCUUUCCAAAACAGCUACACAAAUGCUUCUGAAUGCCCUGGAUACGCAGACCGAGUGGCAGUCUGGCUAAAGGCCCAUCCAGCACUAUUGUGCCCAAGAGCCUUACCGGGCAUUCCCUGAAGCCCCCUCAUAGGCAGUGAUCCUAGACCAAACUCUUAAAUAGAAUCACUUUUGUUUCCUAGAAGAGAUCAAAGAGUGGUUGCUUCUUACUUUGAAGAUGAAAUUAUACCAAGUUAGGUUUUUUGCUAUCUAUUGAUCCAAAAAAUAUAUUCGUGCAAUUAAAGUUAAGUGUUCAACUUAGUAUUUCAAGUUGGGAUUCAGGUUGAGGCAUUUUCCUGCAGAAUGGGCAAUUUUAUGCAUUUAUAUUCAUCAGUGCUGCCCUCACUUUGGAUCUAUUGUAUUCUUACAGUUUAAUCAACUGGCAAAGUGCUUUCAUGCUUUGGAGAUUAACUAUAAAAGCAAGAUUAAGAAAAAUAUGUUAAUUACCAUAUCCCUGGAACUCCUUCUCAGGCUGGUGGGGGCAGCCUUGCAAGAGAAACAGCAGCCUUUGUCUCUUCCCUCUUGUGGGGAGCAAGGAGGGGAUGAGCGGUACCUUGGGAGACCCGGUAAAAGUCUAAAGAAUUGAGAAUUUGACUAUCUUGGGGGUAAAAUGCUGUCAUAGGGGCAGCAGUCUCAGGGGGUGUAAACUCUGGAAUCCACUAUGGUUUACCUUGAGUGGCCUGCACGAACAUGACAGCCCUGAUCUGUAUUUCCUUUCCAUUCAGAAAACCUUAAAAAAAAAAAACUUGUUUUAUGAUAAUAUUAUAACAAUCAUAACUAACAUUUACUGUGCCCGGCAGCAAAUUAAGUAUUUGACAAACAUUAUUUCAUUAAACGAGACUGUCAAUCAUUACUCAAAGAAUGAUGAAGGUAUUUGGUGUAUGCCAAAGAAUAAAGGCGUUUUAUUUCACAGUGA